AGAACCUAGGCCCUCCCCUGCCUUGCUCCACACCUGGUCAGGGGAGAGAGGGGAGGAAAGCCAAGGGAAGGGACCUAACUGAAAACAAACAAGCUGGGAGAAGCAGGAAUCUGCGCUCGGGUUCCGCAGAUGCAGAGGUUGAGGUGGCUGCGGGACUGGAAGUCAUCGGGCAGAGGUCUCACAGCAGCCACAGACCUCAAAGGCUCCAUAUCGCUCUGCUGCGAAGACAAUGAAAAAGGGGUGGCUACGGAACGGUGUCUGGUUCCCCUUGUCCUUCCACCCCAAGCUGCUGGGGCCUGGCCAGCUCUCAAGAGGAACCUGGGGCCCGCUCCUCCCCCCUCCAGGCCAUGAGGAUUCUGCAGUUAAUCCUGCUUGCUCUGGCAACAGGGCUUGUAGGGGGAGAGACCAGGAUCAUCAAGGGGUUCGAGUGCAAGCCUCACUCCCAGCCCUGGCAGGCAGCCCUGUUCGAGAAGACGCGGCUACUCUGUGGGGCGACGCUCAUCGCCCCCAGAUGGCUCCUGACAGCAGCCCACUGCCUCAAGCCGUGGGUGUCACUCACCUCUCCCACCCAUGUCUCCCCCGACCUUUCCUCCUCCAACUACUGUCUCUCCCACCUCAGCCGCUACAUAGUUCACCUGGGGCAGCACAACCUCCAGAAGGAGGAGGGCUGUGAGCAGACCCGGACAGCCACUGAGUCCUUCCCCCACCCCGGCUUCAACAACAGCCUCCCCAACAAAGACCACCGCAAUGACAUCAUGCUGGUGAAGAUGGCAUCGCCAGUCUCCAUCACCUGGGCUGUGCGACCCCUCACCCUCUCCUCACGCUGUGUCACUGCUGGCACCAGCUGCCUCAUUUCCGGCUGGGGCAGCACGUCCAGCCCCCAGUUACGCCUGCCUCACACCUUGCGAUGCGCCAACAUCACCAUCAUUGAGCACCAGAAGUGUGAGAACGCCUACCCCGGCAACAUCACAGACACCAUGGUGUGUGCCAGCGUGCAGGAAGGGGGCAAGGACUCCUGCCAGGGUGACUCCGGGGGCCCUCUGGUCUGUAACCAGUCUCUUCAAGGCAUUAUCUCCUGGGGCCAGGAUCCGUGUGCGAUCACCCGAAAGCCUGGUGUCUACACGAAAGUCUGCAAAUAUGUGGACUGGAUCCAGGAGACGAUGAAGAACAAUUAGACUGGACCCACCCACCACAGCCCAUCACCCUCCAUUUCCACUUGGUGUUUGGUUCCUGUUCACUCUGUUAAUAAGAAACCCUAAGCCAAGACCCUCUACGAACAUUCUUUGGGCCUCCUGGACUACAGGAGAUGCUGUCACUUAAUAAUCAACCUGGGGUUCGAAAUCAGUGAGACCUGGAUUCAAAUUCUGCCUUGAAAUAUUGUGACUCUGGGAAUGACAACACCUGGUUUGUUCUCUGUUGUAUCCCCAGCCCCAAAGACAGCUCCUGGCCAUAUAUCAAGGUUUCAAUAAAUAUUUGCUAAAUGA